ACGUGACAAGCGCUGCCGGCCGCGGUGUCUUCUUCGUGCCGGCGUCGCAGUGGCCGGGCCUCUUGCGUCUGGUAACGCCGCUGUCUCUAACGCCAGCCCUUGGCGCCCGCGCCCCGCCACCGCAGCGCCCGGCAGUCCGCGGCCCAACCGCCGCCCGCGCCCCCGCUCCCCGCACCGUACCCGGCCGCCUCGCGCCAUGGCGGCCCCCGGCAGCGCCCGGCGACCCCUGCUGCUGCUACUGCUGUUGCUGCUGCUCGGCCUCAUGCAUUGUGCGUCAGCAGCAAUGUUUAUGGUGAAAAAUGGCAACGGGACCGCGUGCAUAAUGGCCAACUUCUCUGCUGCCUUCUCAGUGAACUACGACACCAAGAGUGGCCCUAAGAACAUGACCUUUGACCUGCCAUCAGAUGCCACAGUGGUGCUCAACCGCAGCUCCUGUGGAAAAGAGAACACUUCUGACCCCAGUCUCGUGAUUGCUUUUGGAAGAGGACAUACACUCACUCUCAAUUUCACGAGAAAUGCAACACGUUACAGCGUCCAGCUCAUGAGUUUUGUUUAUAACUUGUCAGACACACACCUUUUCCCCAAUGCGAGCUCCAAAGAAAUCAAGACUGUGGAAUCUAUAACUGACAUCAGGGCAGAUAUAGAUAAAAAAUACAGAUGUGUUAGUGGCACCCAGGUCCACAUGAACAACGUGACCGUAACGCUCCAUGAUGCCACCAUCCAGGCGUACCUUUCCAACAGCAGCUUCAGCCGGGGAGAGACACGCUGUGAACAAGACAGGCCUUCCCCAACCACAGCGCCCCCUGCGCCACCCAGCCCCUCGCCCUCACCCGUGCCCAAGAGCCCCUCUGUGGACAAGUACAACGUGAGCGGCACCAACGGGACCUGCCUGCUGGCCAGCAUGGGGCUGCAGCUGAACCUCACCUAUGAGAGGAAGGACAACACGACGGUGACAAGGCUUCUCAACAUCAACCCCAACAAGACCUCGGCCAGCGGGAGCUGCGGCGCCCACCUGGUGACUCUGGAGCUGCACAGCGAGGGCACCACCGUCCUGCUCUUCCAGUUCGGGAUGAAUGCAAGUUCUAGCCGGUUUUUCCUACAAGGAAUCCAGUUGAAUACAAUUCUUCCUGACGCCAGAGACCCUGCCUUUAAAGCUGCCAACGGCUCCCUGCGAGCGCUGCAGGCCACAGUCGGCAAUUCCUACAAGUGCAACGCGGAGGAGCACGUCCGUGUCACGAAGGCGUUUUCAGUCAAUAUAUUCAAAGUGUGGGUCCAGGCUUUCAAGGUGGAAGGUGGCCAGUUUGGCUCUGUGGAGGAGUGUCUGCUGGACGAGAACAGCAUGCUGAUCCCCAUCGCUGUGGGUGGUGCCCUGGCGGGGCUGGUCCUCAUCGUCCUCAUCGCCUACCUCGUCGGCAGGAAGAGGAGUCACGCAGGCUACCAGACUAUCUAGCCUGGUGCACGCAGGCACAGCAGCUGCAGGGGCCUCUGUUCCUUUCUCUGGGCUUAGGGUCCUGUCGAAGGGGAGGCACACUUUCUGGCAAACGUUUCUCAAAUCUGCUUCAUCCAAUGUGAAGUUCAUCUUGCAGCAUUUACUAUGCACAACAGAGUAACUAUCGAAAUGACGGUGUUAAUUUUGCUAACUGGGUUAAAUAUUUUGCUAACUGGUUAAACAUUAAUAUUUACCAAAGUAGGAUUUUGAGGGUGGGGGUGCUCUCUCUGAGGGGGUGGGGGUGCCGCUGUCUCUGAGGGGUGGGGGUGCCGCUGUCUCUGAGGGGUGGGGGUGCCGCUCUCUCUGAGGGGGUGGGGGUGCCGCUUUCUCUGAGGGGGUGGGGGUGCCGCUCUCUCUGAGGGGGUGGGGGUGCUGCUCUCUCCGAGGGGUGGAAUGCCGCUGUCUCUGAGGGGUGGGGGUGCCGCUCUAAAUUGGCUCCAUAUCAUUUGAGUUUAGGGUUCUGGUGUUUGGUUUCUUCAUUCUUUACUGCACUCAGAUUUAAGCCUUACAAAGGGAAAGCCUCUGGCCGUCACACGUAGGACGCAUGAAGGUCACUCGUGGUGAGGCUGACAUGCUCACACAUUACAACAGUAGAGAGGGAACAUCCUAAGACAGAGGAACUCCAGAGAUGAGUGUCUGGAGCGCUUCAGUUCAGCUUUAAAGGCCAGGACGGGCCACACGUGGCUGGCGGCCUCGUUCCAGUGGCGGCACGUCCUUGGGCGUCUCUAAUGUCUGCAGCUCAAGGGCUGGCACUUUUUUAAAUAUAAAAAUGGGUGUUAUUUUUAUUUUUAUUUGUAAAGUGAUUUUUGGUCUUCUGUUGACAUUCGGGGUGAUCCUGUUCUGCGCUGUGUACAAUGUGAGAUCGGUGCGUUCUCCUGAUGUUUUGCCGUGGCUUGGGGAUUGUACACGGGACCAGCUCACGUAAUGCAUUGCCUGUAACAAUGUAAUAAAAAGCCUCUUUCUUUUUGGGGUGGGCCUUGUCCUUCUGUCAGCUAAAAUGGGAGCUCAUGAGAGAAGGACGUCAGGGAAACGGGGUUGAGGGUGGUCUCGGUGCAGAGAGAAGGGUGUCAGGGAAACGGGGGGUGAGGGUGGUCUUGGUGCCAGACGUAGGGAAUGGUGUUGGGAGUGGCCCGAGUGCCUGGCACAGUUGUCUGGUUCAUUCAUGUAACAUGAUAAUUUUUAAAUCAUUAAAAAAAUUACCUUUCAUACAGA